GCAGAAGCCCGAGCCCUGACCCACCGGCGGCUGCGGCGGAGCCGCGCCGGCGCCCCCCAUGCGCCAGACGGCAGGACGGCGGCGUCGGGGGGCGCCAUGGCCUCGGCGGCGGCGGGCGAAGCGGAGGAAACCACCCGGUUGCGCAAGCCGCGCUUCUCAUUCGAAGAGAACCAGAUCCUGAUCCGCGAGGUGCGCGCCCACUACCCGCAGCUCUACGGCGCGCAGAGCCGUCGGGUGAGCGUGGCAGAGCGGCGGCGCGUGUGGGACGGCAUCGCCGCCAAGAUCAACGGUAUCACCAGCUGGAAGCGCACGGGCCAGGAGGUGCAGAAGCGCUGGAACGACUUCAAGCGCCGCACCAAGGAGAAGCUCGCUCGCGUGCCGCACUCCACGCAGGGCGCCGGGCCCGCCGCGGAGGACGCUUUCUCCGCGGAAGAGGAGACCAUUUUUGCCAUCCUGGGGCCAGGUGUGGCGGCGCCGGGGGCAGGUGCUGGGGCGGAGGAGCCCCCUGCGGCCCCCUCUUCACAGCCGCCGCCCCCAAGCGCCUGCCCUCAGCGCUACGUGUUGUCGGAAGACCGCCGGGAGGACCGACGUGCAGGAUCCAGCAGUGUGGUGCAGUAUCCAUAUAGUUCAGAACCUCGUCAAAUGUUGGCCCUUGUCCGAGCGCAGUGGCUCACACCUGUAAUCCCAGAACUUUGGGAGGCCGAGAUACAUCAGCCCACAGCAAGGCGGGCUCCAGCAGCCCGGAGCCAUGGGCCCGGCCCUCCUGCACUCCCCAGGAAGGGGGCUGCCCACGGCCCAAGGAGCGUGAGUCACCACCCCCUUCGGCCCUGCAGCCGGUCCAGCUGCCUCGCCUGGCCUUGUCUCCACCACCCCCAGCCCCUCCACUGCCACCCCCACCGCCACUGGCCCAAGUGGCACCCUCACCCCCUAGCCCCCCACCCCCUCCUCGGCCUCCACCCACGCUCUCGGCCUCAGACCCCUCCCUGGACUUCCUGCGGGCCCAGCAGGAGACUGCCAACGCCAUCCGGGAGCUGGCCGGCACCCUUCGACAGGGACUGGCCAAACUGAGCGAGGCCCUCAGCGCUCUGCUGCCCCUUCUGCCAGGAACCCCAGUUGACUCCCUGCCUCCACCUCUGCCCCCACCCCCACCCCCACCGCCACCUCCCAGGCCUGUCCUGCCCCCACCGGCCCCCAAGGUGGAGAUCACCCCAGAGCCCGUGUCCGUGGUGGCUGCUGUGGUGGACGGGGCAGUGGUGGCAGCCAGGGGAGUGAUCAUUGCCCCAAGGAGCGAGGAGGGGGCACCCCGGCCCCCCCCAGCCCCGCUCCCUCCGCACGACUCCCCCCCACACAAGCGGAGAAAAGGUUUCCCUACACGGAAAAGGCGCGGCCGAUGGAAAUCUCCGUGAAAUCUACUAUCUAUGAUCCUGCCUGCAACCCCUCUCCCCAGCUUGGCGCAGUCGAGGGGGGCGAUGCUCUCUGCCCAUCCCAGCUGCACCCUAGCUCCCUGCUCCAGGGAUGUGAGCACCCACUCCCUGUGCUAGUUAGUGCCUGAUUCUCUGGGGGGGGCCUCAGUAAUGGGCCCCCCCAACCCCUUUCUCUGGUACAGUGCUGUCUGCCUGGCUGCCUCCCUUAACCCUGACUUCUAAGCCAUCAAUUUCAUGUUAUUUAUUAUUGCCCUAUGUGGGGUGGGGAGGGAACCUCUCGGGUCUGCACAUCUCCCCUUCCCUAACAGUUCCUGUUCUUGACUUGAAGAGAAUUGACCCGUGGGGGACUCCCCACCUCCCCAACCCAGACUUUGGAGCGGGUGGGAGUUGUAAGACAAAUCAAAAUACGGAUGACAAAGAGGAUAUAGCCGUGUAUACCCCAGGGAGAGGAGGCGCCGAGUUCUGAUGGGAGAGGUACAGGUUGGGUUCUCUGCCUACCAUUGCUGUCUCUGACUUCCAGAGCUCAACCCCCUCCUUUCUCCCAGUGGUGACAAGAUAUCAAUAAACUUAUUUUUAAUACAA